ACGGCCCCGCUCCCAGUGACCGGAAUGCAGAGGCGUACAUGGCUAAGAGACGAGCUACCUGGGACACAAAGAUGAGAACCACAAGCAUGAGAACAUGAGGAUAAAUACACUUUGGGGAAAAAGAAAACAGACAGAGGCAGCAGAGAAGGAAGACGAGAAGAAGAGAAAAAGAGAAGUAGGAAGAGGAUGAAUUCAUUUCGCUUAUCUGGCAAAUGUGUAAUCUGAGUAAUAGAGAUGGUGCAAUGCUGGGCCACAGAGCUUGCCCCAGGUCCCCAAGCAAAGUCAGUGGCACUGCCUGGACUGGAAGUUCAUCCCCAUCCAUUUUCACGUGCGGAGUCUCAGGGCUCAGUAAAGAACCAUGAUUGACGGAGGUCACACAGCAACUGGUAUGACAGGGACAGGUUUCCGGAAUUCCAGUGUCUUAACACCAAAGCCUGUAGUAUUUCUCAGAGAGAACAACACCACUGCUCGUGUGUGCUCAGAAGAAAGUUUAGUGGUCGUAACAUCCAAUACAUCCAACCUGCAGAUCAAUACACAAAGACCCUGGAGGAAGGUGGGGCGGUAACUUGUCCAAAUCUCCAAAGAAAAGAUAUGGCUGCAAAUUGCACAUCCUCAUGGAGUCUAGGAGAAUCCUGCAACAGACCUGGGUUGGAGCUGCCACGGUCUAUGGCAUCCUCAGAAACUCAACUUGGAAAUCACGACGUGGACCCUGAGAUUUCUCACGUGAACUUCAGGAUGUUCAGCUGCCCGAAGGAGUCGGACCCCAUCCAGGCUCUGAGGAAACUCACUGAGCUGUGCCAUCUGUGGCUGAGGCCCGACCUCCACACCAAAGAGCAGAUCCUGGACAUGCUGGUGAUGGAGCAGUUCAUGAUCUCCAUGCCCCAGGAGCUCCAGGUCUUAGUCAUGAUGAACGGUGUGCAGAGCUGCAAAGACCUGGAGGACCUGCUACGAAAUAACAGAAGACCCAAGAAAUGGUCUGUGGUCACCUUCCACGGAAAGGAAUAUAUUGUGCAGGACUCAGAUAUCGAGAUGGCUGAAGCCCCCUCCAGUGUCAGAGAUGAUCUGAAAGACGUGUCCAGCCAACGGGCCUCCUCGGUGAACCAGAUGCGUCCAGGGGAAGGCCAGGCCCACCGAGAGCUGCAGAUCCUGCCCAGGGUCCCUGCAUUGUCCAGGAGGCAGGGAGAGGACUUUCUGCUACACAAGAGUAUUGACGUAACAGGUGACCCAAAGUCUCUGAGACCCAAGCAGACCUUGGAGAAGGAUCUGAAGGAAAACAGGGAAGAGAACCCAGGACUGACAUCCCCAGAGCCUCAGCUUCCAAAGAGUCCCACAGAUCUGGUGAGAGCAAAGGAGGGGAAGGACCCCCCAAAAAUAGCCUCUGUGGAAAAUGUGGAUGCUGACACACCUUCUGCCUGCGUUGUGGAGAGAGAAGCUUCGACUCACAGCGGGAACAGAGGAGACGCUCUGAAUCUGAGCAGUCCCAAAAGAAGCAAACCAGAUGCCUCCUCCAUUUCCCAAGAAGAGCCUCAAGGAGAAGCCACACCUGUGGGCAACAGAGAAUCCCCGGGACAAGCUGGGAUGAAUUCAAUUCAUUCCCCAGGCCCUGCGAGCCCAGUCAGUCACCCGGAUGGCCAAGAAGCCAAGGCACUGCCGCCCUUUGCAUGUGACGUGUGCGAGAAGAGGUUUACGUGUAAUUCCAAGCUAGUCAUCCACAAGAGAUCACACACAGGCGAGAGACUCUUUCAAUGUAAUCUCUGUGGGAAGCGCUUCAUGCAGCUUAUUAGCCUCCAAUUUCACCAGCGAACCCACACUGGCGAGAGGCCCUACACGUGUGACGUCUGCCAGAAGCAGUUCACCCAGAAGUCCUACUUGAAGUGUCACAAGAGAAGCCACACAGGGGAGAAGCCCUUCGAAUGUAAAGACUGCAAGAAAGUUUUCACCUACAGGGGGAGCCUGAAGGAGCACCAGCGCAUCCACUCCGGAGAGAAACCCUACAAAUGUUCCAAGUGUCCAAGAGCCUUCAGUCGGCUGAAAUUGUUAAGACGCCACCAGAAAACACAUCCAGAAGCUACUUCUCAGUGAUUGCAUAAUCCGGUCUAUGCCUUCUGCACCAAGAAGAAGUGAAUGAUAUUUUUCAUCAAUGUUAUCAGAUGACAUUUGACACAUGCAAGGGCGUCUGACACACAGAGGGAGUGCCCUAGAUAUGAAUUGCCAGGAUGUUUGAGUAAAUAUGUGUCCUCCCCACUGAGCUUUGUUUUCUGUUUCAUUAUGUCCAUUGUUUUCUUAUAGGUUUAUUUUGGUUUGUGUUGCUGUUCUUCCAAUAAACGAUCAUCUUAUUAGUUUUCAAUAUUGUA